GUAGGGGGUGGCGCUCUCCGUUCGGCGGCGCUCCCAUGGCGCACAUUACCAUUAACCAGUACCUGCAGCAGGUGUACGAAGCCAUCGACAGCAGAGAUGGAGCAUCUUGUGCAGAGUUGGUGUCUUUUAAACAUCCUCAUGUUGCAAACCCACGACUUCAAAUGGCCUCUCCAGAGGAGAAGUGUCAACAAGUCUUGGAACCCCCUUAUGAUGAAAUGUUUGCAGCUCAUUUAAGGUGCACUUAUGCAGUGGGGAAUCAUGACUUCAUAGAGGCAUACAAGUGCCAGACCGUGAUAGUCCAAUCAUUCUUGCGAGCAUUCCAGGCCCACAAAGAAGAAAACUGGGCUCUGCCUGUCAUGUAUGCAGUAGCGCUUGACCUUCGAGUGUUUGCCAAUAAUGCAGAUCAACAGUUGGUAAAGAAAGGAAAAAGCAAAGUUGGGGACAUGUUGGAAAAAGCAGCAGAGUUACUGAUGAGCUGUUUCCGGGUCUGUGCCAGCGACACUUCUGCAGGUUGCACAAGAAGCAUGGUGCUCGUAUCUGCUUCUGGUGAGGCCUCAGGCUGCUUCCACUCAUGCUGGAAGACAAAGAGGAGCCCACUACAUGGCAAGAGAGGAGGCAGGAGAUAGAAGGGGAGGCGCCAGGCUCUUCCACAACCAGCUGUCUGGGAACGCUCACAGGAGCUCAGAGCGAGAACUCAUUCAUUAUGGCAAGGACAGCACCAAGCCAUUCAUGAGGGGUCCACCCCCAUGACCCAAAAACCUCCCAUUAGGUUCCUCCUCCAACAACGGGGAUCAGGUUUUAACAUGAGGCUUGAUGUGGCCAAAAAACCACAUCCAAACCAUAGCAGUAGCCCAGCUUCUCUUUUCACUCAUUGUGUUUGUUGCCAAUAAACUCUGUAGCCUCAAAAGAUGGGAACUUUUCCUUUUGGGUGUUGUGGAUCCCAUCCAUGAAACCGAAAGUAAGUGUUGAGCAGAGCAAGCUGUAUGUAAAGGCCAAGGAAUGAAGAAGCAGGAGUGUGGCUCACAAAUCAACUUCUCUACUCCUGAGGGGUGAGGGGAUUGAAAUAGAGGGUUUCUUGAAUGAAGGGGUUGGACAUUGAAAGCAAGGGGAAGAAUAUUCAUGGCUUUUCUGGAAAUGGACGGUGAACUUCUGGGAGCUGAAGCACUGCCAUCUUUUUGUCCUUUUACGGCGUCUUCCCGUCAUUGUCAUGGUGAUUGUCAGCCGCUGUGGCACUGGUGGGAGUGUCACGGAGCAUGCAAAUGAGGUUGUAAUGAAGUUGGAGGCCCUGCAAAGGCCAGGUGGACUUCCACUUAGCAUCCUGCUGGUCUUAGCUGGUUUAACCAAGAGGGGAGCCUCUGACCUCAGGCAUCCUAUUGCUGAAGAUAGGCAGAGUUUGAGUUGUGCAACUGUUCAGCCAAGCCUACAAGAUGUAUAGUGCUGUGGGGGUAACAUGGCCUCCCUACCCAGCCUCGCUUCAGAACUUUCGUACCAAGGCUGGACUGUAGAAAAGUCCUUCCUAUGCCAUGGCACUUUCCCACUGAGGCCUCCCAUGGGUGCCGUUUCCUUUGCUGGAAGGUUCUCCUCGACUCCUGGCAGUCUAUACUCAUUUAAAGGUUUCCGCCUUCUCUAAAGCCUCUCACUGCUGGACUUCACGGUGGAUCAGAUUUCCCUUUUAUAAACAUUCAUAGCAGACUGUACAUUUCUUUCACUGCGUUUACCAAACGAUUUGAUGGCGAAGUGCGUCAGGGCGUGGGCCUUCUCCAUCACUAGCGUUCCUUGCACCCCAGGAGCUCAAUCCGUGUUUCCUAAAUGAAUACUUGACAUUUCGCUUGAUCGUAUAUUUUUGCACAGCAGUGAUCUUCACGACCUUUGAUUAGGCAGUGGCUUCUCAGAUACGACAACAAAAGCAUAAGCAACCAAAGGAAAAAAUUAAUUGGACUUCAUCAAAAUUAAAAACUUUAGACUUCAAAGGACAUUCUCAAAAAAGUAAAAAACAACCAUAACCUAGCAAAUAAUACAUCUGAUAAGGGCCUAAUAUCCAGAAUAUAUAAAGAAUUAUUACAAUUCAACAGUAAAAAGACAAUCCAAUUCAAAUUCUUUAAAAUGUUUAAAGAAUUUGAAAAAUCUUCCAAACAAAAUACGCAAGUGACCAGUAAGUGCAUGAAAAGAUGCUCAAGGUCAUUAAUCACCAGUGACUUAGUCACCAAUGACUAAUGCAUCAGUCACUUGAAAUGCACAUCAGAACCUCUGAGAGCUGCCAGGCCACACCCAGUGGGAUGACUGUAAUCAGAAAGACGGGCGGCGCCAGUGAGGAUGCAGGGAGACUGGAGCCUCGUACACAUCGCCAGGGGAACAAAAACAGUGCAGCUGCUGUGCGGAAAUGGGAAGGCAGUUCCUGAAAGUGGGACGUAGAGCUACCAUGUGACCCAGCAUUUCCACCCUGAGGGGACACUCAGAAGACAGGGCAGAUCCCCAGUGACAUCUCUUUCCCGUUGGGGUUUGCUUUUGUCACAGUCUCCAAUAGAGGUCAUCAUUCCUGGUGCCAGACCAGCUACGAUAUUACCAUGCGUGUAGCGUUUUACCCGUGCUGGUAUAGAGGACUCUAAGAAGUGGGGCAUGCUGUUUCUGGUGAACCAGCUGUUUAAAAUCUACUUCAAGAUCAACAAACUCCAUUUAUGUAAACCCCUAAUUAGAGCAAUUGACAGCUCAAACCUGAAAGACGAUUACAGCACUGCACAGAGAGUAACAUACAAAUACUACGUUGGACGCAAGGCUAUGUUUGACAGCGAUUUUAAGCAAGCUGAGGAGUACCUGUCAUUUGCCUUUGAGCAUUGUCACCGUUCUAGUCAGAAGAACAAAAGGAUGAUUCUGAUCUAUUUGCUUCCAGUAAAAAUGCUAUUGGGUCACAUGCCCACUGUGGAGCUCCUGAAAAAGUAUCACCUGAUGCAGUUUGCGGAAGUAACCAGAGCUGUGAGCGAGGGCAACCUGCUGCUGCUGCACGAGGCGCUGGCGAAGCACGAGGCCUUCUUCAUUCGCUGCGGAAUCUUCCUCAUCCUGGAGAAGCUGAAGAUCAUCACCUACAGGAACCUCUUUAAGAAAGUGUAUUUGUUACUGAAAACACACCAGCUGUCUCUGGAUGCUUUUCUGGUUGCCUUGAAGUUCAUGCAGGUGGAGGACGUGGACAUUGACGAAGUUCAGUGUAUUCUGGCUAACUUGAUAUACAUGGGACACGUCAAAGGCUACAUAUCGCAUCAGCAUCAGAAGCUGGUGGUCAGCAAGCAGAACCCAUUUCCUCCCCUGUCCACGGUGUGUUGAAAGUACACGGAGCCCCGAGGACGGGUGAGCAGUUGUUUCUUUCCACUUUGGUUGUGCUGAUGAGACCGGUCCGGUACUGCAACAAGGCUCCCUGAAGCCGGAACUCUUGGAGGCGCUUUUCCCAGGGAUGCUGAGGCUGAGAUUUUCAGCACACCCGAGUUAAUCUCCUUCAUUUGUAACUAAUUUCAGCCUGAUGAAAACCUGGAAUUCCUUUUUCACAGACUCGGCUGGUUCUGGAGUCUUUGUGAGACUUCUUUGAAGGAGGCUUUGCGUGAAGGCUGCUCGGCUCACUUUUCCUAAGUGUGGUUCCUGAAGGCUGUCUUUGUAACUUUUUGUAGUUCUUUGUGUAAAAAGCGUAUUCUGAAUUUAUACACAUGGCAUGUUCUUCAUUAUAUCUUCCAGGAUACAUCUAUUUUUAUAUAUUAAAUUUGAAUGUGUUAUCAAAAUGCUUGGUUAACUUAAGGCACCUUUUUAAAAGCAGAAUUUAAUUUGAUUUAAAUUUUCCAGAUUUUAUAGCUUGCCUGUAUGGAUGCUCCUCAAUUUAUGAUAGGGUUACAUCCCAAUAAACUUAUUUUAUUUGCCUUUGCUUUGUUGGUUAAAAAAAAAUUUCUUUUAAAAAACCAUCUUAAAUUGAAAAUACAUUUAAUACACCUGCUACUAAA